CUCCUUUUAGCAUAGGGGCUUCGGCGCCAGCGGCCAGCGCUAGUCGGUCUGGUAAGGUAAGUCGAAGUAGGGGAGAAGGGACAGGCCCCAGCGCUUGCAGCCCGCUCCCUCUAGAAGGGUGCGUCAGAGGGUGGGAUCUGGCAGCUCGGGGAAGUGGGCGCAGCCUGGAGCCCCCUUACCCGCGUCGCAGGCGCGCGAGACUCCUGCUGGCCCUCAUUGCCUCCGGGGGCUACCUUAUGCCAGGCGCCAGAGGGGGGCUGGUUGGGGCGGGAGCUGCGGGGGUUUCCGGGGGCGGGGAUGAGUGCAGCUGGGCUCAGCUCCCCGUGCCCUACCUUUCUGUUCUCUUCCUUGGUUUCCCCUACUCUCCUCCUGCCCCAAGCAGUGCCUGAUGCCGAGUUCCGUCUCUCGCGUCUUUUCCUGGUCCCAGGCAAAGCGGAGCGGAGAUCCUCAAACGGCCUAGUGCUUCGCGCUUCCGGAGAAAAUCAGCGGUCUAAUUAAUUCCUCUGGUUUGUUGAAGCAGUUACCAAGAAUCUUCAACCCUUUCCCACAAAAGCUAAUUGAGUACACGUUCCUGUUGAGUACACGUUCCUGUUGAUUUACAAAAGGUGCAGGUAUGAGCAGGUCUGAAGACUAACAUUUUGUGAAGUUGUAAAACAGAAAACCUGUUAGAAAUGUGGUGGUUUCAGCAAGGCCUCAGUUUCCUUCCUUCAGCCCUUGUAAUUUGGACAUCUGCUGCUUUCAUAUUUUCAUACAUUACUGCAGUAACACUCCACCAUAUAGACCCGGCUUUACCUUAUAUCAGUGACACUGGUACAGUAGCUCCAGAAAAAUGCUUAUUUGGGGCAAUGCUAAAUAUUGCGGCAGUUUUAUGCAUUGCUACCAUUUAUGUUCGUUAUAAGCAAGUUCAUGCUCUGAGUCCUGAAGAGAACGUUAUCAUCAAAUUAAACAAGGCUGGCCUUGUACUUGGAAUACUGAGUUGUUUAGGACUUUCUAUUGUGGCAAACUUCCAGAAAACAACCCUUUUUGCUGCACAUGUAAGUGGAGCUGUGCUUACCUUUGGUAUGGGCUCAUUAUAUAUGUUUGUUCAGACCAUCCUUUCCUACCAAAUGCAGCCCAAAAUCCAUGGCAAACAAGUCUUCUGGAUCAGACUGUUGUUGGUUAUCUGGUGUGGAGUAAGUGCACUUAGCAUGCUGACUUGCUCAUCAGUUUUGCACAGUGGCAAUUUUGGGACUGAUUUAGAACAGAAACUCCAUUGGAACCCCGAGGACAAAGGUUAUGUGCUUCACAUGAUCACUACUGCAGCAGAAUGGUCUAUGUCAUUUUCCUUCUUUGGUUUUUUCCUGACUUACAUUCGUGAUUUUCAGAAAAUUUCUUUACGGGUGGAAGCCAAUUUACAUGGAUUAACCCUCUAUGACACUGCACCUUGCCCUAUUAACAAUGAACGAACACGGCUACUUUCCAGAGAUAUUUGAUGAAAGGAUAAAAUAUUUCUGUAAUGAUUAUGAUUCUCAGGGAUUGGGGAAAGGUUCACAGAAGUUGCUUAUUCUUCUCUGAAAUUUUCAACCACUUAAUCAAGGCUGACAGUAACACUGAUGAAUGCUGAUAAUCAGGAAACAUGAAAGAAGCCAUUUGAUAGAUUAUUCUAAAGGAUAUCAUCAAGAAGACUAUUAAAAACACCUAUGCCUAUACUUUUUUAUCUCAGAAAAUAAAGUCAAAAGACUAUGAUAUCAUAGUUUUUUAUACCUUAUUUAAGAGAAACAACCUGACGUGCACCAAUCAGUCUGCACAUCCCAACCCUUCACAUUUUAUAAAUUAUUGUAGAUCAUGUUUUGUUAGGAGCACUUUUAUGAGAGACAUUUUCCAUGACUAAAUAAUCAGCAUUAGUCAGUAAAUCCUUUAGAACUGGGUUUUGAAAUGGGAGUUUUAUCAUAUUAAAUCAUUUCUUGUAGUCUUACAUUUUUUGUUGUUGUUCUGGAAUCUACCUGUAAAGGAAAGUAGACCUGGAUUCAUGUGGGCUCUUCCAUGGCUUAAGUGUUGCCCAAGAGAUUUUGUAGGUAACGAUUUUUUUUUUUCUGGCCACAAUGCCAGAUACUAAGCUAAUUGGUCUAUCAUACACAUGCUUGCAGUAGUUUCAUGAAGUUUAGUCUCUGGCGUGAAAUUUUAAUCACCAAUGAAGGAGAGAGGCACCUGUAGGUAAAUUUACUUUAGUCAUAUUUUAUAUAAAACAAGGGUUAGUAUUCAUGUAACAUUGAGAAGUUUGGGAAUAACAGCAGAUAUGAUUAAUAAAAGUCAUAACCAUACUCAAGAGCUUCUUAGAUUUUCAUUUAUGGCAAGUUAUAAUUACAUGUAAAAGUAGUCUUGAACAGGUAAAUAUUGAGCCUUUUUAAUAGGAUGUAACCUUUGUAGAGCCCAAAUUCUAAAGAACAAAAUUGGCAAUCCAAUUAAACUACAUGCAAAAUAAGUGUGAUA